GCAGUUUCCGGCGUGAGCGGCGAAAGCCGGGAGGGCGAGCGAGAGAGCAAGCAGGCAGCAGGCUGCCGGCGGGCGGGCGGACGGCACAGAGGGAGGGAGCGAGCGAGCAGUGAGUAAGCCAGCAAGGGCGGUCGGGUCCCGAGGUCAGCCGAGAUUUCUCAGGUCCCUCCGGCCCCCUCCCUGGAGUCCACAGCGCCUCCGGUGUCCAGAGGAUCGGACACGGCCCGGCCCGGCCAUGGCCUCGUUGCUGAAGGUGGAUCAGGAAGUGAAGCUCAAGGUAGCGGCACCGGUCCGGCCUUUUUGCCCCUCGCUUUGAUCCCCCAGCAGUCUGACCGGCUUCCUACUCCCCAUGGCGUCUUUGUCUCCCUGGGGAUACCAGCUCUGAGCUUCCGCUCGGCUCAGCCCAGCCCCCAACUCCCGGGGUCGGCUUCGCGGGAGAGGAAAAUAUAGGAUGGCUUUCUGUACCGCGUCUGAUGAUGGAGAGUCCCGGGGACACCUCCGCGGACACGUGUUGGACUCAGGGCUUUAGGCCCGUGACAGCUGACAGCUUCAGACACAGGAGGAAGGGAGGGAAGGGGGAGGACAGAGGAGACAGGCAGGUGCUGUCCUCAAAGCCCUGCGUUCUUCUGAGAUGGAAAAAUGGAUCCUCAAAAAAAUAAAGUAUUUGCAGUCUGGGGGCCUCUCAGCUUCUUAUUACAGUUACAAGGUUGAUUCUUUCAGGGAGCGGAUCACAAGUGAGGCAGAAGACUUGGUGGCAAAUUUUUUCCCAAAGAAGUUAUUAGAACUUGAUAGUUUUCUGAAGGAACCAAUCUUAAACAUCCAUGACCUAACUCAGAUCCACUCUGACAUGAAUCUCCCAGUCCCUGACCCCAUUCUUCUCACCAAUAGCCAUGAUGGACUGGAUGGUCCCACUUAUAAGAAGCGAAGGUUGGAUGAGUGUGAAGAAGCCUUCCAAGGAACCAAGGUGUUUGUGAUGCCCAAUGGGAUGCUGAAAAGCAACCAGCAGCUGGUGGACAUUAUUGAGAAAGUGAAACCUGAGAUCCGGCUGUUGAUUGAGAAAUGUAACACGGUCAAAAUGUGGGUACAGCUCCUGAUUCCCAGGAUAGAAGAUGGAAACAACUUUGGGGUGUCCAUUCAGGAGGAAACAGUUGCAGAGCUAAGAACUGUUGAGAGUGAAGCUGCAUCUUAUCUGGACCAGAUUUCUAGAUAUUAUAUUACAAGAGCCAAAUUGGUUUCUAAAAUAGCUAAAUAUCCCCAUGUGGAGGACUAUCGCCGCACCGUGACAGAGAUUGAUGAGAAAGAAUAUAUCAGCCUUCGGCUCAUCAUAUCAGAGCUGAGGAAUCAAUAUGUCACUCUACAUGACAUGAUCCUGAAAAAUAUCGAGAAGAUCAAACGGCCCCGGAGCAGCAAUGCAGAGACUCUGUACUGAGGCCAGGGCCAGGGCCAGGGGACUCUGUGAGUCUGGCUCAAGACCGACAUUGCCUUGGUUUGUUACAUGACUAUCGUGAUGGGGAAACUGGCUGGAAAUAGUAAUCACACCUCUCUGUUUUUAGUUAGAGUCUAAUGAAACUCUCAUCUAGUUCUGUGAUGUGUUUACCUCUUUUUUCAGGCCUCAGGAACUCUUCUAUUUCCUUCCCUAAUACCCCACACCCAACCUGUCGUAAUUUCUGGAGAACUCCAGGUUUGUGUGUGCAGGAUGUUGGCACAAAAAUACCUGUGUUUUCAUUCUCCCCCUCUCUCCCUCCUGUGUCUUGCGCUUUAUGUUUUCUUCCGUUUGAUAAUUAGUUGGUUAAAAGCUGAGGGAACCGGAAGGAAAGUGCUAGGUGUUUUUUAGGAACUAGGGUGGCGGGGGGACGAACUUCUCUUCCUCACAUGAGGUUACUGUUUCUUUCCUCUGUGGGGCAUUGGAUCCUCCCACAGUUGCCCUGGUGAUGACUUAGGGCUUCCCAUCUGUGUACAUCCCACUUUGAAUCUUGAUCGUGACAAGAAAUACCUUAGGCCUUCAGUCAAUUCCGAAGCUCCUUCAGUUGUUUUUAUAAUGGGCGUUUUCACAUGCACAUAUGUGUAUGCAUGUAUACGCCCAUACAGACAUGCACACACAGACUCCUACUCCAUUAGCUAACAUACCCUCCCUCUCCACAACCCCUGUCACAUACCUUUCAGGAGGUGACAGUUGUCUUAGUUGUCAUCUACCCAGACAAACGUCCUGGGCCCGUCCUCCCUCCUGAUACUGUAGCCUCUUGGUACCCAGGGUGAGUUGGUGGAGAACAGAGAGAUGAGAAGCAGAGGGCUUGGGGAAAGCCUGUUCCUCUCUGACUCAGCCCUUUUUGGCAUUAUUGCAAGAGCUUGACUCCUGGUUGCCUUUUCCCAGCCAGUUUUCAGUUGGGGUGAAGGUUUCUGCAAGUGUGAGGUCCAGAUGCUGCUGCUCAUGUUGGGCUUUCCUUUUGGGAACUAUUUCUCUUUAUUUAUAGUGUCGGGCUUCCGGGGAAAGCAAUCAUUGGUGUGUAUGUGUAUGUGCAUGCACACACGUGCAUAUACACAUUUGUGUAUGUGGAAAUGUGCUGGGCAAGUCAAAACUAUAGAAGAGUUGCCUCCUGUCUCUCGAAUCUUCCAGAGAUAUCACUUAAUUGUUAACAGCUUUUGUGUUAAUCCCCUUCAGCCCCUAGCUCUUUUAUUCUACCACGGCUGGAGAGUUGAUACCUGCAGUCAGCCUGCCAGUGACUCUUAGUGUCUGUUUCUGACUUAUUUUUCCUGUCUCUGUCUUCCAACCCCCAAUAAUAUUUCCACCGGGGAUGCAUCAUUUUUACUCCCAAUAUUCUGUAGAGAGGGAGUCAGGAUGCUGUCUUCCCACGAAUAGUACUCAGUAACAAACCAAUUGCAUUUUAGUUGGGCAGUGCUCCCACCCACCCUCCAGAUCCCUUCCAGCUAAAACCCUUCCCCCUUCCCUCCAUGUGUUUCUCAGUUUCCCGUUUCGUUUGUUGGACUGUUCCACUGCCCCUCCUCCUCACCCUAUCACCCAUGGAUCGUAAUGUAAAAUUCUUUUACCAUGUCAAGAAAUUAUUAAAAAUACAGGUACUUUGACCUCUUUCUAAAGCCGCAGACCCUGGUGCAAUGCUCUGGUGGCUAGGGAUGUACUCAUGCUCAUAUGUGUGCACGCUUGGACACCCACCUCCAUGGACACCUAGCCACCCUGUUGUGUGUCCUUAUGCCAGUUGAGCUGAAUCUUUUCCCCAGUAUAGUGGAAAGACUGAGGCUUCUGCCUACUGAGCAAGGUUGGGUGCUUCAUUUGUGUUCAGUCUGAAUUAUGGGAAAGUUAGCUCUUCCCAGACCUAAGCUGCCUUCUCUCCCUACUUUCAGAAGAUCCUAGUUCCUUCCUUCCCGAGUGAUACCCAUGAACUGCCAGUAGAGGCUGCUAUCGUUCCAUGUGUAAGGAAUGAACUGGUUCAAGGCGCGUCCUACCCAGUCAUUUUCUUUACCUUAUACUAAUUCUUCCUGAAUAAUGUCUUCAGUUUCUUGAGGAGACUCCUAGUUUUGGUUUUCAAAUUACUUGGAGGGCUGCCUAGGAAUCUAUCUCCCUCUGAAAUAAAGUUUCCUCAUCUUCCACCUUGCAA